GUAGUGGUGCCGACUUCCUGUUGUUUGAGGCCGGGUUGGGGGUGUGCGAUUGUGUGGGACGGUCUGGGGCAGCCCAGCAGCGGCUGACCCUCUGCCUGCGGGGAAGGGAGUCGCCAGGCGGCCGUCAUGGCGGUGUCGGAGAGCCAGCUCAAGAAAAUGGUGUCCAAGUUAUAGAAGACAUAUGGGAAGCCAUAGAAGAUUGUGACCCAGUACAAAUACAGAGACCUAACUGUACGUGAAACUGUCAAUGUUAUUACUCUAUACAAAGAUCUCAAACCUGUUUUGGAUUCAUAUGUUUUUAACGAUGGCAGUUCCAGGGAACUAAUGAACCUCACUGGAACAAUCCCUGUGCCUUAUAGAGGUAAUACAUACAAUAUUCCAAUAUGCCUAUGGCUACUGGACACAUACCCAUAUAAUCCCCCUAUCUGUUUUGUUAAGCCUACUAGUUCAAUGACUAUUAAAACAGGAAAGCAUGUUGAUGCAAAUGGGAAGAUAUAUCUUCCUUAUCUACAUGAAUGGAAACACCCACAGUCAGACUUGUUGGGGCUUAUUCAGGUCAUGAUUGUGGUAUUUGGAGAUGAACCUCCAGUCUUCUCUCGUCCUAUUUCGGCAUCCUAUCCGCCAUACCAGGCAACGGGGCCACCAAAUACUUCCUACAUGCCAGGCAUGCCAGGUGGAAUCUCUCCAUACCCAUCCGGAUACCCUCCCAAUCCCAGUGGUUACCCAGGCUGUCCUUACCCACCUGGUGGUCCAUAUCCUGCCACAACAAGUUCUCAGUACCCUUCUCAGCCUCCUGUGACCACUGUUGGUCCCAGUAGGGAUGGCACAAUCAGCGAGGACACCAUCCGAGCCUCUCUCAUCUCUGCGGUCAGUGACAAACUGAGAUGGCGGAUGAAGGAGGAAAUGGAUCGUGCCCAGGCAGAGCUCAAUGCCUUGAAACGAACAGAAGAAGACCUGAAAAAGGGUCACCAGAAACUGGAAGAGAUGGUUACCCGUUUAGAUCAAGAAGUAGCCGAGGUUGAUAAAAACAUAGAACUUUUGAAAAAGAAGGAUGAAGAACUCAGUUCUGCUCUGGAAAAAAUGGAAAAUCAGUCUGAAAACAAUGAUAUCGAUGAAGUUAUCAUUCCCACAGCUCCCUUAUACAAACAGAUCCUGAAUCUGUAUGCAGAAGAAAACGCUAUUGAAGACACUAUCUUUUACUUGGGAGAAGCCUUGAGAAGGGGCGUGAUAGACCUGGAUGUCUUCCUGAAGCAUGUACGUCUUCUGUCCCGUAAACAGUUCCAGCUGAGGGCACUAAUGCAAAAAGCAAGAAAGACUGCCGGUCUCAGUGACCUCUACUGACUUCUCUGAUACCAGCUGGAGGUUGAGCUCUUCUUAAAGUAUUCUUCUCUUCCUUUUAUCAGUAGGUGCCCAGAAUAAGUUAUUGCAGUUUAUCAUUCAAGUGUAAAAUAUUUUGAAUCAAUAAUAUAUUUUCUGUUUUCUUUUGGUAAAGACUGGCUUUUAUUAAUGCACUUUCUAUCCUCUGUAAACUUUUUGUGCUGAAUGUUGGGACUGCUAAAUAAAAUUUGUUGCAUAA